CUGGCCAGCCCACCAUGCACGCCCACUGCCUGCCCUUCCUUCUGCACGCCUGGUGGGCCCUACUCCAGGCGGGUGCUGCGACGGUGGCCACUGCGCUCCUGCGUACGCGGGGGCAGCCCUCGUCGCCAUCCCCUCUGGCGUACAUGCUGAGCCUCUACCGCGACCCGCUGCCGAGGGCAGACAUCAUCCGCAGCCUACAGGCAGAAGAUGUGGCAGUGGAUGGGCAGAACUGGACGUUUGCUUUUGACUUCUCCUUCCUGAGCCAACAAGAGGAUCUGGCAUGGGCUGAGCUCCGGCUGCAGCUGUCCAGCCCUGUGGACCUCCCCACUGAGGGCUCACUUGCCAUUGAGAUUUUCCACCAGCCAAAGCCCGACACAGAGCAGGCUUCAGACAGCUGCUUAGAGCGGUUUCAGAUGGACCUAUUCACUGUCACUUUGUCCCAGGUCACCUUUUCCUUGGGCAGCAUGGUUUUGGAGGUGACCAGGCCUCUCUCCAAGUGGCUGAAGCACCCUGGGGCCCUGGAGAAGCAGAUGUCCAGGGUAGCUGGAGAGUGCUGGCCGCGGCCCCCCACACCGCCUGCCACCAAUGUGCUCCUUAUGCUCUACUCCAACCUCUCGCAGGAGCAGAGGCAGCUGGGUGGGUCCACCUUGCUGUGGGAAGCCGAGAGCUCCUGGCGGGCCCAGGAGGGACAGCUGUCCUGGGAGUGGGGCAAGAGGCACCGUCGACAUCACUUGCCAGACAGAAGUCAACUGUGUCGGAAGGUCAAGUUCCAGGUGGACUUCAACCUGAUCGGAUGGGGCUCCUGGAUCAUCUACCCCAAGCAGUACAACGCCUAUCGCUGUGAGGGCGAGUGUCCUAAUCCUGUUGGGGAGGAGUUUCAUCCGACCAACCAUGCAUACAUCCAGAGUCUGCUGAAACGUUACCAGCCCCACCGAGUCCCUUCCACUUGUUGUGCCCCAGUGAAGACCAAGCCGCUGAGCAUGCUGUAUGUGGAUAAUGGCAGAGUGCUCCUAGAUCACCAUAAAGACAUGAUCGUGGAAGAAUGUGGGUGCCUCUGAUGACAUCCUGGAGGGAGACUGGAUUUGCCUGCACUCUGGAAGGCUGGGAAACUCCUGGAAGACAUGAUAACCAUCUAAUCCAGUAAGGAGAAACAGAGAGGGGCAAAGUUGCUCUGCCCACCAGAACUGAAGAGGAGGGGCUGCCCACUCUGUAAAUGAAGGGCUCAGUGGAGUCUGGCCAAGCACAGAGGCUGCUGUCAGGAAGAGGGAGGAAGAAGCCUGUGCAGGGGGCUGGCUGGAUGUUCUCUUUACUGAAAAGACAGUGGCAAGGAAAAGCACAAGUGCAUGAGUUCUUUACUGGAUUUUUUAAAAACCUGUGAACCCCCCGAAACUGUAUGUGAAAGUUGAGACAUAUGUGCAUGUAUUUUGGAGGUGGGAUGAAGUCACCUAUAGCUUUCAUGUAUUCUCCAAAGUAGUCUGUGUGUGACCUGUCCCCCUCCCCAAAGAUUAAGGAUCACUGUAUAGAUUAAAAAGAGUCCGUCAAUCUCAUUGCCUCAGGCUGGGUUGGGGGAGCCCCACAGCUUUCUGGCUGGCCAGUGGCAAUCUACUGGCCUUGUCCAGAGGCUCACUGGAGUGGUUCUCUGCUAAUGAGCUGUACAACAAUAAAGCCAUUGUCUAGUUCUCCUGGGCCAGCUGGUGCCUGUGAAGGCAGAGGCAGGAACUCAUCCAAGAGGACCGGCCAUGUUGGGUUACAGAAGACAUCCCUGCGUCAGUCUGCUUCGGCAGACACAGCCUGAGUUUGUUAAAGUUGGUGACAAUCCACCUCAGUCUCUCAAUGUGUGCUAUUAAUGAGGCCUCUGAGCUUCCUAUCCAGCAGUGGUGAAGGCCUUGCCCUGGGUGGCAAGAUACUUGCUCUAUGGUCACAGCUCAGCCACUGGAAGCUGUGCGACCUCAGGUGAGCAAUUCACUGUCCAGUCUCCACUUGUAAAAGGAACGCUGGUGAAUCCUAAUGCAUUCAUAUUAAAUGUCUGUUGUCAGGCUCAGAAGAGCCAUGAGCUUU